AGAAGUUGGCAAGGUUGUGUGUAAGGUCGGGUGGGGUGGGGUCAGCUCUCCCGAUUAAUGCAGCUAUUUGAUAAGAGCAACGUCGCGGGACGCUUGCCGUCUUUAUGGGGGCGGGGAGAAGGGGCGCGGGUGUCGCUGCGGGAGAGUUACCGUAUUUGCGUUGAGCAGCGCAGACUGUAGAGCAAAGAGCUGCGGCCGGAGACCGGAGGAGCAGGGGCUCAGCUGGGCUGGACUGGUGAUUGCAGCUGGAAGUGCCCAUGACCGAGCUGGCGUCCUCCGGGGGCGGGUCCCCUGCGGGGGACGGGGAGGAGGGUCUGGGGGACGAGCGAGGCCUGGUCAUCCACCACCCUGCAGAGGAGCAGCCCUACCGCUGCCCGCUGUGCGGCCAGACCUUCUCGCAGCAGCCCAGCCUGGUGCGGCACCAGAAGGCGCACGCCGGAGCGGGCCGCGCGGCUGCCUUCGUGUGUCCCGAGUGCGGCAAGGCCUUCAGCGUCAAGCACAACCUCGAGGUGCACCAGCGCACGCACACCGGGGAGCGGCCCUUCCCCUGCCCCGAGUGCGGCCGCUGCUUCAGCCUCAAGCAGAACCUGCUCACGCACCAGCGCAUCCACAGCGGCGAGAAGCCGCACCAGUGCGCGCAGUGCGGCCGCUGCUUCCGCGAGCCGCGCUUCCUGCUCAACCACCAGCGCACCCACGCGCGCAUGCCCGCGCCGCACCCGCGCCGCCCCGGCGUCUUCGGGGAGCGGCGGCCCUACUUCUGCCCCCGCUGCGGCAAGAGCUUCGCGCGCGAGGGCUCGCUCAAGACCCAUCAGCGCAGCCACGGCCACGGGCCCGAGGGCCAGGCGGCCCACUUAGGACGCGUGCUAUGAUGCGCCCGGGGCCUGCUGCCGACGGCUGCUUCCCGCCCCGCACGUGCGUCCCCGACCCCUGGAGAUGGCCCUGGGCCGCAGCUCCCUCUCUAGAUGGGAUCCCGGGAGAGGGGCAGCGCUGGCUUGGGCUCUUGAAGGUGUGGGCCGCCGCCAGGCUCCGGCCGCCCGCUCGCGUUCCUCCCUCGGGACCCUCUGGCUGGCUGCGCACAGCUGCUUCCGGCUCCUGCCAUGGUUCUCCUUCUCUGGCCCAUCCGGCCUAGAGCAGUUGCAGAGUGGGCAGGAUCUUAAGACCCGAUAGGUGCAGAACCCAUCUGGACACGGAGACCAGGAAUGGAGUUCCAUGGAGGCCUGGCUGGCACUGCACCCGGGCAUGAGGACACAUCCAGUAAGAAGACCUGCCUCAAGAGGUGCACUGCGGUGACCAGUGGAGGUGACUGGUUGGAGCCUGGAAUUGGAAGCAGAUUCCAAGCUCUGGUGGACAAACUCUCCAGGCCUGGUGGGAAUCACAGCUGGGGCAGACCUCAUCCUGGCUGCCUGGCCACAGGCCCCCACUCUCUGCCACUGGUGGUAGGACGAUGCCUGUGUGGAGAGCUGGCUUCUCUGCUCCCGCCUGGUCCACCACUUGGCUAGAGUUCAGAGACAGGAAGUGAUUGGUCUAAGCUAACACAGCAAGUUGGUGGCAGACCUGGUUCUAGAGGCAAAACCUUCUUCCAGAUGUGAAUGAAACCUGCAGGCUUCAUUUUCCUUUCUGAGCAGUGCUUCUUAGCUCUUUGGAGACACGAAGCCCUUGGAAAAUCUGAUGAAGGUUACGGACCUUCCCUAGGAAAACAGAUAACUGACGUAGACUCAAAAACCCCAAGCAAUUUCAGGAGCCACUGGACUCCCUGAAUGAAACCCAUCCCUGGACUCCAGGCUAAGAACCUCAGCCCUGGGGACUUCACCUGCUGCCCUUUCCUUACCUGUCACACAUUGAGCCCCGAGUCAAGGCCACUGUACAAGUAGUGCCCCUCCCUCCCCCUGGCCAAGCCUCCUUCCCUUGUUCAGGAAUAAAGAAUUCCGAGGAGCCCUUUUUAGUCAUUCCCUUCUCCCAGACCUAACGAAUGGUGCGUCAGGUUUCUGGAGCCUCAUUUCCCUUCCCCAGACAUUGGCAGAGGUCCCUUGGGCUAGAUUUUCUCUUCUGGUUUUGUUUCUUGUUCUGCCUGACUGGCCGCUGGCUUCCACAAAGGAGCCCUUUGCUCCUGGCCUGGGCUCUGAUUUCACUGUGUGGUCUCAGGGGAAGCUGGACUGCUGUGGACGCUGGUGGGAGCUUGAGUCUGGUCUGAGUCUGCCCCAGGGAGAAAGAAUCCUGCUUCCACCAACCAAGCCCAGUCAGCGGUUCCUCCCAGCUGGCCAAGUGUUCAGCCCAGUGGGCUGGGGAGGAAGAGGAUGAGGGCCUCGCUCCUGGUGCCUGUGGCUCUGGGCAGGGUGAGAGGUCGGUGGAGGAUCUUUCUGUGUGUUCUCUGAGUAUGCAGCAGUGCAGUUGAAGGGAACAGGGCCCAGGCAGGCAGCAGGGCAAGGACUCCUCCCAUCUUCACACCUGAACCAGUCAGCCUGGAAGCUACAAGUUCUCACCUGCCUCCCCAGAAUGAACAUCAGAAAAGGCAAAACUGACCAGGGCUGGGAUGGGUUUGGGUCAGCGUGGUUGGAGGGCAGCCUGUGGAUCCCUGCACUGGAGUCUUGCUGUCUUCGAUGCAGGUUGGAUCAUACAUUGUUACCUCCUACUGUAUGCCUCACCCUGGAAUAGCAGAAUGCUCAGGGGGAGAUCCGAGAACGAGAAGGUGCUCCCAGCCCCAGGAGCUUCCAGUCUGGCUCUGAUCCUUGGCCGACCUAGAGGAAACCUCCACACACGCCCCUUUUGUGCUAAUGGUGCAGUUUGUGUCCCCCUCUGCCCAUCACUGUGCUGUGCUUGUUCCUGCCUCUGUGCCUUCCCCUAUACUGCUCGGACAUGUCCCCUUUCCUCUCCUCUACCCAGCUAAGCCCUUCUGAUCCACGGGGCCCGGCUUCCCAAACCACCCAGCCCACAUUCCUCCUUCCUGCUCCGAACAGGUCCGGUGUGAGCCCCUGCCCCCGAACUGCGUGCUGUCCCAUGGACGCUCCAGUCUCUUCCGUGUGUGUCUUGAGUCCCUAACUAGACAGUUAGCUCCCUGAGGGCAAGGGACUGUCAUUUCCUCUUGAGUCCUACCAGGGUCUAGCACAGGACUGGGCUCCUAACUCUCAGGAAACACUUGUCGGCUGACUGGUGCCUCAAGCGCUGGAGCUUGUCGGUGGCCGGUAAUGGGCAGUGCACGUGGGGAGAGGGUAUGUGAGUUAACUCAAGGGUGCCUUUUCUUGGGCUGUGGGCUGGCUCCCCUGGGUCAAAAGUGGAUGUCGGAGGCCUCAGGCUCUUACCUCCUUGGGGCAGUGGGAGCAUCAGGGACCCCCACCCCCACCCCGGCUCUGCAGGAGUGCACGGAAGUGGUCGUCCAGCCUGGAUAUUUCUACAGGUUGCUGACUCCUGCGGGAGCUGACUGAGUGGAAUAAAUGUUCUCUCAACAUCA